ACCAGAAUUUUUGGAAAAGUAUCCACUGUGAUGGGCCUCUCUUCCUGGAGAACAGACGCCUUUGUCCUACUUGCUAGGAAGAUAUUUUUCCUGCACUGUUUUUGGGUUUUGGUUUUUGUUUUUUGGCACUGGAAUGACCCGGAGUCACCCGGGAGCUCCCAAGAGGAGGAUGCAGGGUCCCAGGUCAACUAUAUUACUACUCAUGGCUGCCACUUACUGAGGGCCUAAUACACAUCAGACACUCUGUCGUGUGGAUUACAUAAGCUGACACUUAUCUUUCCAACGGUCCUGCAAGUUCAAUGUCAGUCAAAUUUUACAGGGUGUAAUCUGGAGCCGGAGACUUCAAGAUACUUGUCCAAGGUCACACAGAUAUUUACUGACAAAGCUGGGACUUGACCCCAGGUCUGACUAAAACGUGGGCGCACCAUGCACCACCCUGGCACCUGAGAACCCCUCCCAGCCUUAAUGGAGCCUUCUGUGUCUUGCACCCAGUCCCUAGCCCCCAGAUAUUCCUGCUGUCUUAAUUGUUAUUGAUUGCUGCAUAAAAAACUACCCCAAGCAUAUCAAGUUAAAAUGAUAAGCAGUUUUUCUCUGAGAGUUCUGUAGAUCAGGGAUCCGGGUAUGGCUUAACUGGAUCCUCUACUUCCCAGUCUCUCACAAGGCUGCCAGCCCAGGGACAACAGUCUCAUCUGUAGGCCUGACUGGGGAAGGAUUGACUUCCAAGCUCACUCAUGCGGCUGUUGGCAGGAUCCAGUUCCUCAUCUGUAGGCUCAGCUGGGGAAAGAUAGACUUCCAAGCUCACUCAUGUGAUUGUUGGCAGGCUCUAGUGGGUCGCUGGCCUGAGGGCCUCAGUUCCUCUAUGGCUGUUGGCCAGAGACUUUCAUCAGCUCCUCGCCAGCUGGCCUUCUCCAUCUGGGCAAACACGCGUGCAGGAAGAGCCUGAGGGAGAGAAUGAAUGCCAGCAGGUCAGAAGUCACAGUCUUGUUAUAGCCUAAGCAUGGAAAUGACACGCCAUCACCUUUGCCAAAUUUUGUUGGUUAGAAGCAAGCCACUAGGUCCAGCCCACCCUCAAGGGGAGGGAAUUCCAUAGGAGCAUGGGUGCCAGGAAGGGGGAUCCUUGGAAGCCAUUCUGGAAGGCUGCCCACCACACCUGCUCCUGCACCCACCUCAGUAUAGUGAGCCCCUUUGGGUAUCAACCACCUUGACGGAGCAAAUGGUUGAUGGGCCACCUUGGACUGUGCUAUGUGGCCUGCAUCUAUCUGAUCCCACCUCUCUUCCAGCAGGCCCAGGACUCGAGUCUGCCUGGCCUUGCCUUCCUCCCCAAACCUACCAGCUACUCCUGGCCACUGAGCCCAUGAGAUGUCACAGCAGCUGAAAAGGGACCUGCUCCCUGUGACUGAAGCACACACCCAUCACUCGGGUGGGACUGGGACCCAGGAUGGUGCUCCAGGCCUCUCCUGGUAAAACAGAGGUGAAGGGCUCAGCUCUCCCACUGAGACAGGGCCCACCUCAGGAGAACACGGGUACAGGUGGGAGAGGGCUGGGUCCAGAGUUAUCUGUGAAAGCUGCAGAGAUGUUCUUGCUUUUACCCUCUGGGUUGGGAUUCUGGGUAGAAUCCCCCCAAGUUCUCCAGCAGGCAUCACAGAAACAUCUCUAAGGCAACGUGGGAGCACCCAUGCCAGAGAAGGAGCUGCUCUGAAGCUGCGUGGAGACCCAGAAGUGUUCAGACGCCUAAGAUGGGGGACCUACUCUAGGGAGGAGAGGAAGAACGCCUCAGGGUCUUGCCUGCUGUGAGUGCCUUGAAGAGGGAGCAGCGGGCACGAUCAAAGAGACACCUGGCUCAAGGACCAAUAAGGAGUAUGGCUGCCCCUCCCAAAGCUCCCAUCCGUGUCAGGAAUUUGACCAUCAGAGCAGGAGCCCUCACUGGGAAGGAGAACAACAUGCUGCAGCCCGAGACCCACAUCUUCACAGCCCCCGAGGAGGGGAGCUCCCAAGGGGCUCUGCUGCUUGGCCAGGCCCCAGAACCUUUGUCUCUGCCCUGUACUCCAGUGACCUUGGAGCAGCAACUGGUUUCUCCUUCUGGGGAUCCCCACAGGGCCCCUGCCCUGCCCAGCAUAUGCUCAACUCUGAUCCUCCAGCCCUGUGCCACCCUUGACCCUCUUCUACUGCAGCCACAGGUCCCCAAAGUCUCUGACCAGGCUUUGGUUUCUGCCCACUCAGAGUGGCAGCGGAAGCUGGAGGCCGCUGAGGCUCUGCUGACUCUGAGAAACUCUGCCCAGGCCCCUCCUGACUCCAUCUCCCUGCACCAGCCUUGCAACCCACCAGCUCCUGCUGGAGAUAAAGGAUUCCAGCCUCCCAGCCCCUCUCUCCGCCCCAGGCCAGCCAGCUCCAUCUCGCUGCCUAUUGGACAUCUGGGAUGCAUCUCCCUCUUGAGCUAGGAACCCAGAGGAGGAGGCCUCAAUAGAGCACUGCCUAUUUGGUAUCCAGUUUCUGAAUGUGCAAAAUGGUUAACGUCCAAAACGCUUAACGUCUUUUUUUAAAGCCUUCAGGUGUUUUAUAAGCUUUUUAUUAUAUGGGGCAACUCCUUGGCUGAGGGUGGAUAUUCUUGUACCUCUGUCCCUUACUCUUUUGGAUGCUGGGGCCUUUUUCUGUCUCAUAAAGACAGGAUUGUGCAAUCUAAGUUGAUCAGUCUCUCAGUGGGGUUCUGUGUGAGUUCAUAUGCCAGAGUUUUUAUUCGUCUUGUGAUUGCUGACAUACCUGUGCACUCAUGUGUAUACCCCUGCAUGUGGAAACAUGAAGAUGUUUUCACUUUGUGUCUAGGUUUAUGUACGUGAACAAAUAAUAAACCGUUGUUGUUAUAAGGCAC